AGUUGCACAGCUGCCUGGUAGGUGACUGGAGGCAUUGAGCAGUGCUCACUGGUAUUUCGCUGAUGUGGCCCCAACCCCGCCUCCCUCCCCACCCCGCGAUGUCAGAAAAAACACAACAGGGGAAAUUGGCCGCAGCCAAGAAAAAGUUAAAAGCAUAUUGGCAGAGGAAGAGCCCUGGCAUUCCAGCAGGAGCUAACAGGAAAAAGAAAGUCAAUGGCAGUAGCCCUGACACAGCCACUUCUGGUGGUUACCACUCACCUGGGGAUUCAGCAACAGGUGUCUACGGGGAGGGCCGUGCAUCCUCUACUACCCUGCAGGAUCUGGAGAGCCAGUACCAAGAACUAGCAGUGGCCCUGGAUUCAAGCUCCGCAAUAAUCAGUCAACUCACUGAAAACAUCAAUUCACUGGUUCGCACAUCUAAGGAGGAGAAGAAGCAUGAGAUACAUCUGGUACAGAAGCUUGGGAGGAGCUUGUUCAAACUCAAAAACCAGACGGCUGAACCCCUGGCCCCAGAGCCCCCAGCAGGGCCAUCUAAGGUAGAGCAGCUACAAGAUGAGACCAACCACCUAAGGAAGGAGCUAGAGAGUGUGGGAAGACAGCUCCAGGCUGAGGUGGAAAACAAUCAGAUGUUGAGUCUCCUGAACAGGAGACAGGAGGAGAGGCUACGUGAACAGGAGGAGAGGCUACAUGAACAGGAGGAGAGGCUACAUGAACAGGAGGAGAGGCUGUGUGAACAGGAGGAGAGGCUACGUGAACAGGAGGAGAGGCUGUGUGAACAGGAGGAGAGGCUACGUGAACAGGAGGAGAGGCUGUGUGAACAGGAGGAGAGGCUACGUGAACAGGAGGAGAGGCUGUGUGAACAGGAGGAGAGGCUACGUGAACAGGAGGAGAGGCUGUGUGAACAGGAGGAGAGGCUACGUGAACAGGAGGAGAGGCUGUGUGAACAGGAGGAGAGGCUACGUGAACAGGAGGAGAGGCUGUGUGAACAGGAGGAGAGGCUACGUGAACAGGAGGAGAGGCUGUGUGAACAGGAGGAGAGGCUAUGUGAACAGGAGGAGAGGCUGUGUGAACAGGAGGAGAGGCUAUGUGAACAGGAGGAGAGGCUGUGUGAACAGGAGAAGCUGCAGGGCAAGAGGCUGCUGGAAGAGGUGGAGAAGCUGUUAGAACAGGAGAGGCGGCAGGAGGAGCAGGAGAGGCUGCUGGAGAGGGAGAGGCUGCUGGACGAGGUGGAGGAGCUCCUGGAGCAGGAGAGGCUUCGGCAACAGGAUGAGAGGCUGUGGCAGCAGGAGACUCUGCGGGAGCUGGAGAGGCUGCGGGAGCUGGAGAGGCUGCGGGAGCUGGAGAGGAUGCUGGAGCUGGGGUGGGAAGCCCUGUACGAGCAGCGGGCCGAGCCACGCAGCGGCUUCGAGGAGCUGAACAACGAGAACAAGAGCACACUGCAGUUGGAGCAGCAAGUAAAGGAGCUGGAGAAGUCGGGUGGAGCUGAAGAGCCAAGAGGCUCCGAGUCUGCAGCAGCAGCCAGACCAGUACCUGGAGCCCCAGUCCCACAAGGAGCUUGGAUGUGCGGACAAGCAGGGUGGACUCCCCAGGAGCACCCAGGCUUGAGUGGAGAAGCUGUUGGUACAGGAGAGGCGGCAGGAGGAGCAGAAGAGGCUGCAUGCCAUUCUUUUCGGGCUGCGGAGAACAGGGAGCUAAACAUCACCAUCAUCUAAGAGCGGGUCAAGAAAUUGAAAAAAAAAAAAAACAAAACAUUUAAGGGGUUAAUAUCCUACACAAUUCAUUUACUUCAUUUGAAUGUUAGAGCCACUUAUGUUUAUUUGUGUUUCUAAUUUAUAGUUUAAAUUUAUUUGUGUUUCUAAUUUAUAAUUUAAAUUUAUUUGUGUUUCUAAUUUAUAGUUUAAAUUUAUUUGUGUUUCUAAUUUAUAAUUUAAAUUUAUUUGUAAAAAGUUAAAUGAGAGUGGGUCUUUCUCUCAUGUUCACUCUGGCAUCUUUUAGCAUUUUUUUAAUUUGAUAAUUAUAGGACGUUAGCAUGCAUAUCGAGUUUGCCCUUAUGUGGUGGGAGUUCAAACACACAAAGACCCACUGUAUGCACACAACUGUUCUUGCUGGUUUGGGAUAGGCUGCCAUGCUUUUUUAAUGUUAGUACAGCCUGUAUAUUCAUUACGGAAUUCAGAUAAAAUUUCCUUAUGUUCUGCUGUUAUGUUUGAUCGAAUCCUAAUCACAGUGAGCUCUUCAUUAGCUCAAUAUGUGGUUUGCCCUCAAGUGCGCGGUCUAUUACUUUGUAAUAUGCCACUGUGAGUACUGACAUUUACAGUUGUUUAAAGGUGGAGCACUGGAAACAGCCUUUCCCCCUUUUUCUGUGUAUUGGGGAUGGGAGUAAUAACAUUUUGGGGAGGUUUUUAAAUCUCCCAGAAGAGGAAAGUGGCCUGCUUUGGCAGGUGUGUGCAGGAUAGAAUAUGUUUCAUUUGUUCUGGUGCCAAGAAUGAGCGCUGUACUACGGUAGUUCCCUUAGGAUUUGUAUGUGCUCUGGGCUCAUGAAGAUACUGCCUCAUGAGCUGUGGCAGUUGUACUCUUUUUUGAUGACCUGAAAAGGGAUUAUUUCUGAGGAAUGAAAGGCUCCCAUCAUGACUGUGGAUGUGGAAAACCUUUUCUAGCUGAGAGCAUUUAUAUCUACAAUACAUUUUAAAGUCAGAGUUCAUGUUCCCUGUUUUAAUCACAUGACUACAUGUCCCAGUACACAAAAGGGCACUGGUUGGCGUUCUCCUUAAUGUAUUUAGUAAAGAUCAGAAGAAAUCCUUUAAGAGUUUAAAUGCCCCUGGAACAGGCAUAUACAGGCUCUAGUCAAGAAUGAAUUCGAGUGAAGGAAAGCUGUGUGACACCUGGCAUUCCUCUGUGUUCAUGGAGCUUAUUUGAGGCUAGAAGAUGGAUUUUACCAUCUAGACCUCUCUGGCUAAUAGCUAGUCUUCAACCAUCUGACAUAGGAAUUUACUUCUUUUCCUUGAAUGGAGAACACUUUAAAAAUAAUAACAAACAUUAUUAUAAACUAAUAUAUGUGAGAGUACUUAGUUGAAACAAAAAGGAGUUUUAGUAGACAGUAUUAUACUACAUUUGAAAAUCAAGGAGCAGUUUAUGCAACGUAAAAUGUUUACAAACUGCAGCGCAAUCUACUGUUUGUGACUGUCAAAGUGUCAUGAGGAAAGUGUCUAUACAAUCACAGAGUUAUAUUUCCUCACAAAGUUCUUUACGAAGAGUGAAAUAUGUUUUUAUACCUCUCAGUUUCAGUUAGAGGCAUAUUUUGUGUAAUAUUUAUGGCUUAAAAUGGACUAAAGGUCCUGUUCUUGCCUUGUCUGAACUUGCCGCUUUUGCAUUCUUUGAGUUCAGUUUAAAGACACUUACUUUAACUCCAUUUUAAACCCUCGGGCUAGAAAUCGUACCACUGUUAAUUAGCCACGUUAUUUGGUCUAACAGUUUUUGUUUAUCAUUCUGAAACUGAGCUUAUCUAAUACAUUGAUAAAUUAUUUCAAAGGUAUUUUUAUAGUUCAAAUCGCUUCACUUUUACCCUGACACGUAUAAAUGACUAGGAAUGACCUUCAGAUAGCGUUUAGCAACUGUAACCAAUCUGACAAUAAUGUGUUCAUCAGGUACCUGUGGAUUAAAUCACAUACUGGCAUAUUUAAGCUGAAUGUCAGUCUGAAAAAUAAAUGUACUAUAUUAACUCAAAUACCACUCUCUGUGUAGGUAUUUUGUCAUAUGUUUAAGAAAAAGCUAAAGAGAAUGGAAAUCCUAUGACAAUAACUCAAGUCUUUCUUCAAAGUGCAUGCAGUCUCUUGCAGUACCUCAUUCAGCCAAGUAUUUGUUCUCUUCCUCAUUCAGUAUAAGGCAGCUUUCAAUUUGCUUAGAAGGCAAUAUUAGAAGGUUAGAGUUCAGCAGAAAGAGAGAAUUUUAAAAUGUGAGUUCGACUGAAUAAAUUUGAAUUUCUGUAGGAAGUAAAGAAUCAAAAUACCUAUUUAAAGACUGCAAUAUAUGAUAAUUAUUUUUAAAGUAAUAGAUUAAACCUGAUAGGUUUUCCUGAAAUGAAAAACAAUCAGUUCUAAAACCAAAGCUGAUUUUUAGAAAAUGUGAAAAUGUAAAUCAACCCUAUCCAAAAUAGAUUCUCUAAAACUUUAUCUUACAGUCACUUUCAAAUAACUAUUCAAAAAUGUAACUGUUAAAUUAAUGUCUUAAAAUAAUUUAAAACAUUUUAAAAUACGAAUACUGUAGCUUAAAACAAAGAAUCUAGGGGAAGGAAAAGUAGAGAAAGAAAUGCCAAUUCCAGUCCAAAGCUGUAUUUGCCAAGUUUUCUUAGAACGACUUUUACCGAUUUAUGAAUUCUUAUACACAGAAUGCAUGAUGGAAAUACUGAUUUUUGUCUAAAGUGGCAUUAUUGACUGCUUCUGUGAUGCUACUGUAAUGUAAUAAAUUAUUAGAUUGUUUCAAGGUGC